AGAGGCAGAUGGAAGGCAGAGGCUGCGCAGAGAAUGGAGAGCUGUGUCUGAGGAGCCUUGGAACAUUCACCCAGGAAACUCCAGCACCUCCUAGAACAUCUUUUGUGGAAUGGCACCUCAUGGGGGCCCUUGGAUCAUGUACCCCUUGUAUUCAACAGUAAACAUCUUCCUAUAAUCAUUGCUUCAUUAACGAUAAUGUGAGCCAAUGCACAGUAUUUAUCAAAUGGCAUCUAAGAUGGUUAAAGCACACCUAAUCCUCUCGUGGGUGCCUGCCAAGAGUAGAAAAGGGUAGUGUAUAGAUAUCAAUUUUAUUGUCCAGCAUUCCCUAAUCGAAGUCCCAAGUGGUCUGAAAACUUAGACGAAAGAUAAAUGGGCCGCAGUAAUUAACCACUGCAAUAACAGAUGUUAUACAGGAAACCUGUGUGUGCCAGAGCUAUAAGCAUGUUUUGAUUUUGAAUACGCACUUGGGCUAGCACAUUCUUCCUCAAUAAUGGAAAUAUGUAAAUGUUUUGUAAGGUAUUAACUGCCAUGGCAGACGUUGAAUUAUUUUUCCUUUAAAAAACAUAUACAUAUGCUUUGUCAGAUAGUCCAAGGACUUCAGUUUCAUGUACAACCUGGAUUUCUUUGGAAUCUGCGGAGUUUCACAUUUUCCCAAGUGUUCACGGUGAAGCUCCUGGCUUCGAGCUGGCUGUCUUCAAGGGUGUUUUCUUGAGCUACCCCUCUCUCUGCUCUGCCAAUUAUGUGCCACUUUGUCUUGGUGCUAUGAUUGCUUUCUUCUGAGAGGGAAAUUCCUCUUUCAUCAGUAUGGAUGCACUGUUUUUACACACUGCAAGUGCUGUGUUACUGUGUCAGUCAUCCUAUUAGGGCCAGUUUCAGACGAGUAGGGCUGACGAGCUGGCUGGGGAUUGGCUGGCCCCGGCUGGGAGGGAUUUGUCGGAAGGAAGGGCUGCAGCUUACAGCAACAGAGUUUAGACUGUCUUUGCUUCAUCAUCUGAAGGUAAAAUUUUCCAGAUACGGCAGACGGCUUUCAGAGUACAAUAAACAGGGAAUGAGAACUAUUUACAUGGAAGUUUCUUUCUCAUGAUGCGGUGGAGAAGCCUCGGCCACUUGGUUCUGCCAGAUGUUCCUGGGGUUACUGUAAAUGGGAAGGACAGGCAGAGCUAAACAAGGUUUAUCAUUUAAAAGUGCCUGUGUGAAGUCACUUUUGCUGGAAAACUGCAGCUUGGGAGCUUUCUUUGUAUUCACAUCCCACUCUUCUGUCAAGUACACUUUACCCUGACCUUAUGAGUGGAUGAAGAUACCUCAGUUGUCUGACUUUGCCAAUUGCUUAAUUUCAGAAUUUAAAAAGGGGAAAGAAAAACAUCCUGCUAAAAUAUGAACAUCUGAGUGUCUUAUUUUCCAACAUCGUCAAUAGCUGUGAGCGUCAGCAUUAAAUAUUCUCCCAAGGAGUGCCAUGAUAUUGAAGUCACUUUAUUAAUAACAGCUGUAUCUGCAAAACAGUCAAGAGACUCGGACGUUGAAAGCCAGAGAUGACACUGAGCAUGCUUUUAUUGCGGCCUACCAUCUUUAAGUGGGACAUAUUGAUUGAUGAGUGAUUGCCUGUCCAUACACUCUCUCAUCAUCCUGUUCCUUGGAUUGGACUUCACUAAGCAAUUUAUCACUCACCUUCAGACUUACAUGUGGGAGUUUUCACAACAGUAGUUUUGGAAUCAUUAGAACUUGGAUUGAUUUCAUCAUUUAACAGAAACAAACAGCCCAAAUUACUUUAUCACCAUGGCUUUGAACGUUGCCCCAGUCAGAGAUACAAAAUGGCUGACAUUAGAAGUCUGCAGACAGUUUCAAAGAGGAACAUGCUCACGCUCUGAUGAAGAAUGCAAAUUUGCUCAUCCCCCCAAAAGUUGUCAGGUUGAAAAUGGAAGAGUAAUUGCCUGCUUUGAUUCCCUAAAGGGCCGUUGUUCGAGAGAGAACUGCAAGUAUCUUCACCCUCCGACACACUUAAAAACUCAACUAGAAAUUAAUGGAAGGAACAAUUUGAUUCAGCAAAAAACUGCAGCAGCAAUGCUUGCCCAGCAGAUGCAAUUUAUGUUUCCAGGAACACCACUUCAUCCAGUGCCCACUUUCCCUGUAGGUCCCGCGAUAGGGACAAAUACGGCUAUUAGCUUUGCUCCUUACCUAGCACCUGUAACCCCUGGAGUUGGGUUGGUCCCAACGGAAAUUCUGCCCACCACGCCUGUUAUUGUUCCCGGAAGUCCACCGGUCACUGUCCCGGGCUCAACUGCAACUCAGAAACUUCUCAGGACUGACAAACUGGAGGUAUGCAGGGAGUUCCAGCGAGGAAACUGUGCCCGGGGAGAGACCGACUGCCGCUUUGCACACCCCGCAGACAGCACCAUGAUCGACACAAGUGACAACACCGUAACCGUUUGUAUGGAUUACAUAAAGGGGCGUUGCAUGAGGGAGAAAUGCAAAUAUUUUCACCCUCCUGCACACUUGCAGGCCAAAAUCAAAGCUGCGCAGCACCAAGCCAACCAAGCUGCGGUGGCCGCCCAGGCAGCCGCGGCCGCGGCCACAGUCAUGACUCAGUCGACUGCCAAAGCAAUGAAGCGACCUCUCGAAGCAACUGUAGACCUGGCCUUUCCCCCUGGUGCUCUUCAUCCUUUACCAAAGAGACAAGCACUUGAAAAAAGCAAUGGUACCAGCGCGGUCUUUAACCCCAGCGUCUUGCACUACCAGCAGGCUCUCACCAGCGCACAGUUGCAGCAACACGCCGCGUUCAUUCCAACAGGGUCAGUUUUGUGCAUGACACCCGCUACCAGUAUUGUACCCAUGAUGCACAGCGCUACGUCCGCCACUGUCUCUGCAGCAACAACUCCUGCAACAAGUGUCCCCUUCGCAGCAACAGCCACAGCCAAUCAGAUAAUUCUGAAAUAAUCAGCAGAAACGGAAUGGAAUGCCAAGAAUCUGCAUUGAGAAUAACUAAACAUUGUUACUGUACAUACUAUCCUGUUUCCUCCUCAAUAGAAUUGCCACAAACUGCAUGCUAAAUAAAGAUGUAGUUCUUCUGGACAGACCACAACUCUAAGAAGCUAGUGCUGCUAUCUCAUAUAUGAGUAUUAAAUAUGGUAUGCUUAGUAUAUUCCAACCUAAGAUAGUUAACUACCUGAGACCAGCUGUGAUGUUUAAAGACAUAAAGGAUAAAGUUUACUUUUAAAGGGUUUCUAAACAUAGUUUCUGUCCUAGGAAUAUUGUCUUAUCUCCAUAACUAUAGCUGAUGCAGAAAGUCCAGCCAGUUUACUCAUUUCGAUUCAGAAUAUUUCAAAUUUAGCAAUAAACAAUUAGCAUUAGUUAAAAAAGAAACAUAUUCCAAGGGCAGGUUCGAUUCUAGCUCUAAUUACUGUCAUGUCAUUUACCCACUGGAUCAAAGGGUAUGUUUCACUUCUUGACAAUAUAAAUGCUGCAGCAAAGAUGAGAGGUGAAGUAAAACCGAUACCUGUCCUGCAGGUCUAAAAUUUGAAUGGAAAUUCAAGCACAAGUACUGGGGACACAUCAAAGUGUGGUGUUUGGUUUGCCUGGAGAUGCCACGUUGAAUCAUGUGAUUCUAGAUUAACAUUAAAUAGAUUGAAAAAGAAACUUUGCACGGUAUGAGCUUCAUACCCCACCAAACAAAGUCUUGAAGGUAUUAUUUUACAAGUAUAUUUUUAAAGUUGUUUUAUAAGAGAGACUUUGUAGAAGUGCCUAGAUUUUGCCAGACUUCAUCCAGCUUGACAAGAUUGAGAGGCCCAUGCCAACAGUCUAAUCUAAGAGAUUAGUCUUUCAAACUCACCAUCCAGUUGCCUGUUACAGAAUAACUCUUCUUAACUAAAAACCUAGUCAAACAAGGAAGCUGUAGGUGAGGAGAUCUGUAUAAUAUUCUAAUUUAAGUAAGUUUGAGUUUAGUCACUGCAAAUUUGACUGUGACUUUAAUCUAAAUUACUAUGUAAACAAAAAGUAGAUAGUUUCACUUUUUAAAAAAUCCAUUACUGUUUUGCAUUUCAAAAGUUGGAUUAAAGGGUUGUAACUGACUACAGCAUGGAAAAAAAUAGUUCUUUUAAUUCUUUCACCUUAAAGCAUAUUUUAUGUCUCAAAAGUAUAAAAAACUUUAAUACAAGUACAUACAUAUUAUAUAUACACAUACAUAUAUAUACUAUAUAUGGAUGAAACAUAUUUUAAUGUUGUUUACUUUUUUAAAUACUUGGUUGAUCUUCAAGGUAAUAGCGAUACAAUUAAAUUUUGUUCAGAAAGUUUGUUUUAAAGUUUAUUUUAAGCACUAUCGUACCAAAUAUUUCAUAUUUCACAUUUUAUAUGUUGCACAUAGCCUAUACAGUACCUACAUAGUUUUUAAAUUAUUGUUUAAAAAACAAAACAGCUGUUAUAAAUGAAUAUUAUGUGUAAUUGUUUCAAACAUCCAUUUUCUUUGUGAACAUAUUAGUGAUUGAAGUAUUUUGACUUUUGAGAUUGAAUGUAAAAUAUUUUAAAUUUGGGAUCAUCGCCUGUUCUGAAAACUAGAUGCACCAACCGUAUCAUUAUUUGUUUGAGGAAAAAAAGAAAUCUGCAUUUUAAUUCAUGUUGGUCAAAGUCGAAUUACUAUCUAUUUAUCUUAUAUCGUAGAUCUGAUAACCCUAUCUAAAAGAAAGUCACACGCUAAAUGUAUUCUUACAUAGUGCUUGUAUCGUUGCAUUUGUUUUAAUUUGUGGAAAAGUAUUGUAUCUAACUUGUAUUACUUUGGUAGUUUCAUCUUUAUGUAUUAUUGAUAUUUGUAAUUUUCUCAACUAUAACAAUGUAGUUACGCUACAACUUGCCUAAAACAUUCAAACUUGUUUUCUUUUUUCUGUUUUUUUCUUUGUUAAUUCAUUUAAACUCAUUGAAAACAUAGUAUACAUUACUAAAAGGUAAAUUAUGGGAAUCACUGAAAUAUUUUUGUAGAUUAAUUGUUGUAACAUUGUCUUUCUUUUUUUUCUUUUGUUUCAUGAUUUUGAUUUUUAAAAUUAUUAGCACACAACUAUUUUCAGCCCUUUAAUAAUGGAGCAUCAAAAACAUCACCUGUAACCCCAAGCAAAUAUAGAAGACUGUAUUUUUUACUAUGAUAUCCAUUUUCCAGAAUUGUGAUUACAAUAUGCAAAGAGUCAUAAAUAUGCCAUUUACAAUAAGGAGGAGGCAAGGCAAAUGCAUAGAUGUACAAAUAUAUGUACAACAGAUUUUGCUUUUUAUUUAUUUAUAAUGUAAUUUUAUAGAAUAAUUCUGGGAUUUGAGAGGAUCUAAAACUAUUUUUCUGUAUAAAUAUUAUUUGCCAAAAGUUUGUUUAUAUUCAGAAGUCUGACUAUGAUGAAUAAAUCUUAAAUGCUUUGUUUAAUUAAAAAACAAAAAUCACCAAUAUCCAAGACAUGAAGAUAUCAGUUCAACAAAUACUGUAGUUAAGAGACUAACUCUCCACUUGUAUGGGAACUACAUUUCACUCUUGGUUUUCAGGAUAUAACAGCACUUCACCGAAAUAUUCUUUCAGCCAUACCACUGGUAACAUUUCUACUAAAUCUUUCUGUAACACUUAAAGAAUUCCCUCAUUCAUUACCUUACAGUGUAAACAGGAGUCUAAUUUGUAUCAAUACUAUGUUUUGGUUGUAAUAUUCAGUUCACUCACCCAAUGUACAACCAAUGAAAUAAAAGAAGCAUUUAAAAGGA